AUUGUUUUCCUCCGCGGAUCCGCGGCUGGACUUGGACCCAGGGCUCUCCCGACAGCGCCCUGGAACCCAAAUUCAAGCACCAUCCAAUUCGGACGCUCAUCGCAUCUCGCCUGAGCACAACCACGGAUUGCGAACUCAGCGCAGCGCGUGGCCGCUGGCCGCCCGCGGCGAUCUCGAUCCCGCUGACCCGAAUCCUGGAGCAACUCUCCUAGACUCUGGCUGUGACCCCAGCCAUUCCCCAGAGGUGGCUUCGGGGCCAGGAGAGAGAAGGGCUGUUUCCUCUUCCCAGCAACGGGAGGAUCUGGAAAGGGGAGAGUCGGCCAGGUCUCUCCCAUGUGCUUCAGAUGGGGUGUGUGAAGCAGCUCGGAUUCUUCCAGGGCAGAGUGAUCUUUUCUCCAGGCCAGGAGUUGAGGAGCUGACCAGAUGCUGCUUCCCAGAAACAGCUACAAGAAGCCCUCUUAAAGGUGUAUCAUAGUUGAGUCUAGAAGGCCAAUGCAAAGGCCAGCCAAGUGUUUGUAGAGGCUGGACUAAUCCAGCCUAAAGUGGGGUGUGAGUGUGUGUGUGUGUAGACUGAGUGGAAGGGAGGCACAGCCUGCUCUCUCAGGGAGGAAGGAAAGGGUUGAGGGUGCUUGCUAUCAGAUCAUUUUGCCUGGAAAUGAAGAGCAUGUAAAUGAGAUGCAAAUUAGCCUCUAUUGUCCCUAGCUAAGGCGCUUUUGCUAAGAAGGCUGUUGGAUUCUGAGGGCCUUAACAUGGGAGUGGUCGCCAUGCCCCACAAACUCUCCCAGUGACCCCCUUUGCCAAGGCUAGCCCUGUAGUUCUAGCAGUUUCUAGAAAGGGGCCAUCCCCUUCCCCUGCAUCUCUGGGCAUAAAGCCACCAGCACCUUUGUAACCAAACUAUUAAGAAGUGUCAUCAGCCCCCUCCCAUUUUCAAGGCAGCAUCUCCCCUACCCAAGCGUCAGCAGACUUUUCUUGAAUUUUUACAUUUACUUGUAAGGGAUGUGGUAAGGGGAGCAUAAUGCAGUCUCUUCUCUCCUUUGUCCUGUCUUCCAUCAGGUCAGAGGUUUCCUAUCCCCCUCAAGCCCCCACAGGAGUCACCAACCCAGGGCCGGCUUAUGGGUGAGGGGGCACCCCCUGGGGCCUGAGCUGCCCCGCACAGGAUGCCCCGUGCCCCCCACUUCAUGCCCUUGCUGCUACUGCUGCUGCUGCUCUCACUUCCCCAUACUCAGGCCGCCUUUCCCCAGGACCCCCUCCCUCUGUUGAUCUCUGACCUUCAAGGUACUUCCCCAUUAUCCUGGUUUCGGGGCCUGGAGGAUGAUGCUGUGGCUGCAGAACUUGGGCUGGACUUUCAGAGAUUCCUGACCUUGAACCGGACCUUGCUAGUGGCUGCCCGGGAUCACGUUUUCUCCUUCGAUCUUCAAGCCGAAGAAGAAGGGGAGGGGCUGGUGCCCAACAAGUAUCUAACAUGGAGAAGCCAAGAUGUGGAGAACUGUGCUGUACGGGGAAAGCUGACGGAUGAGUGCUACAACUAUAUUCGUGUUCUUGUUCCCUGGGACUCCCAGACGCUCCUUGCCUGUGGAACGAACUCAUUCAGCCCUGUGUGCCGCAGCUAUGGGAUAACUUCGCUGCAGCAGGAGGGUGAGGAACUGAGUGGGCAGGCUCGAUGCCCCUUUGAUGCCACCCAGUCCAACGUGGCCAUCUUUGCAGAGGGCAGCCUGUACUCAGCCACAGCUGCGGAUUUCCAGGCCAGUGAUGCUGUAGUUUACAGAAGCCUUGGGCCCCAGCCCCCACUCCGCUCCGCCAAGUAUGACUCCAAGUGGCUCCGAGAGCCACACUUUGUCCAGGCCUUGGAGCAUGGAGACCAUGUCUACUUCUUCUUCCGCGAGGUCUCUGUGGAGGAUGCUCGGCUGGGGAGGGUGCAGUUCUCCCGCGUAGCCCGAGUAUGUAAACGUGACAUGGGCGGCUCGCCUCGGGCCUUGGACCGCCACUGGACAUCCUUCCUGAAGCUUCGGCUCAACUGCUCUGUCCCUGGGGACUCUACUUUCUAUUUUGAUGUUUUACAGGCCUUGACUGGGCCUGUGAACCUGCAUGGCCGCUCUGCUCUCUUUGGGGUCUUCACCACCCAGACCAAUAGCAUCCCUGGCUCUGCCGUCUGCGCCUUCUACCUGGAUGAGAUUGAGCGUGGGUUUGAGGGCAAGUUCAAGGAGCAGAGGAGUCUGGAUGGGGCCUGGACUCCUGUGUCUGAGGACAGAGUUCCCUCACCCAGGCCAGGAUCCUGUGCAGGAGUAGGGGGAGCUGCCUUGUUCUCCUCUUCCCGAGACCUCCCUGAUGAUGUCCUGACCUUCAUCAAGGCUCACCCGCUGCUGGACCCCGCUGUACCACCUGUCACCCAUCAGCCUCUACUCACUCUCACUAGCAGGGCCCUACUGACCCAAGUAGCUGUGGAUGGCAUGGCUGGUCCCCACAGUAACAUCACAGUCAUGUUCCUUGGCUCCAAUGAUGGGACAGUGCUGAAGGUGCUGACCCCAGGUGGGCGAUCCGGGGGACCUGAGCCCAUCCUCCUGGAAGAGAUUGAUGCCUACAGCCCUGCCCGGUGCAGUGGGAAGCGGACAGCCCAAACAGCACGACGGAUCAUAGGGCUGGAGCUGGACACUGAGGGUCACAGGCUUUUUGUGGCUUUUUCUGGCUGUAUUGUCUACCUCCCUCUCAGCCGGUGUGCCCGGCAUGGGGCCUGUCAGAGGAGCUGUUUGGCUUCUCAGGACCCAUACUGUGGAUGGCAUAGCUCCAGGGGCUGUGUGGAUAUCAGGGGAUCUGGUGGGACUGAUGUGGAUCAGGCUGGGAACCAGGAAUCCAUGGAGCAUGGUGACUGCCAAGAUGGAGCUACUGGGAGUCAGUCUGGCCCUGGGGAUUCUGCUUAUGGCGUGCGCCGGGACCUGCCCCCAGCCUCGGCCUCCCGCUCCGUCCCCAUCCCACUCCUCCUGGCCAGUGUGGCCGCAGCUUUUGCCCUGGGCGCCUCAGUCUCUGGCCUCCUGGUCUCCUGUGCUUGUCGCCGCGCCCACCGACGUCGGGGCAAGGACAUCGAGACUCCGGGGCUCCCGCGCCCUCUCUCCCUCCGCAGUUUGGCCCGGCUCCACGGUGGGGGCCCAGAGCCCCCGCCGCCCUCCAAGGACGGGGACGCGGUGCAGACGCCGCAGCUCUACACCACCUUCCUGCCGCCUCCGGAGGGCGUGCCCCCGCCGGAGCUGGCCUGCCUGCCCACCCCCGAGUCCACGCCGGAGCUGCCGGUCAAGCACCUCCGCGCCGCCGGGGACCCCUGGGAGUGGAACCAGAACAGGAACAACGCCAAGGAGGGUCCGGGCCGCUCACGGGGCGGGCACGCGGCGGGCGGGCCCGCGCCCCGCGUGCUGGUGAGGCCACCGCCGCCCGGCUGUCCCGGGCAGGCCGUGGAAGUCACCACCCUGGAGGAACUGCUGCGCUACCUGCACGGCCCGCAGCCGCCCAGAAAGGGGGCCGAGCCCCCCGCCCCUUUAACCUCGCGGGCGCUCCCGCCGGAGCCCGCCCCCGCCCUCUUGGGCGGCCCCAGCCCCAGGCCCCACGAGUGCGCCUCGCCGCUGAGGCUGGACGUGCCCCCCGAGGGCAGGUGCGCCUCUGCCCCCGCCCGGCCCGCGCUCUCCGCCCCCGCUCCCCGGCUGGGCGUCGGCGGAGGCCGGAGGUUGCCUUUCUCCGGCCACCGGGCCCCCCCUGCCCUGCUCACUCGAGUCCCCUCGGGAGGUCCCUCCAGGUACUCCGGGGGUCCCGGGAAGCACCUCCUGUACCUGGGCCGGCCCGAGGGCUACCGGGGCCGCGCCCUGAAAAGGGUGGACGUCGAGAAGCCCCAGUUGUCCCUGAAGCCUCCCCUCGUCGGGCCCUCCUCCCGCCAGGCCGUCCCGAACGGCGGCCGUUUCAACUUUUAAAGGGAGCGGCCCACGGCCUCCAGCGUGGGGAGCGCCCGAGUCCUCUCGGCCACGAGCUGGACGCUCUUCAGGACGUUUCACCGCCCCCUCGCCCCGCACCUCCAGCCUUCCCGACUCGCAGAGUCUCCCGAGGCCCCUUUUCGCCUCGGGUUUAUUUAUUGACUGUCUUUCCCCCUGUCCUCGACAGAAGAGUGGGAGGUGAGAAGCCCGUCUCCUCAGUGAGCCAGCAUUUCAGGGGGAGCUGGCGGACUCCCACUCCCCGCUCCCUUCCAGCCAAGCUGCCUUAACUCGCCCCUCGGGGCUCCCCCAGAGACUGUGCCCCGGGCGGGCCGCGCGCGCUGUGUCCAGAGUCCUCGGGCCUUCUGGGUCUGGGACGUGCCUCUCCUACUGUGUAGGAGCCUCCGCUUCCCAAUACAGCCGUGUCUGCAGCCACUGCCUGACUUCACUCGGGCGGGGGAGGGCGGCAGUCGGUCGGCUCGCUCUGGGCGCCCUCGCUCUCUGCCUUCAUCUGGGCCCUGGGCUCUCCCGGGUAAUGGGAUGGCUGCGGUCCCGCCGGGGGGCAGUCUGGAAAGGUUUCCUAAAGGAGACGAGCGAAUUAACGGUGUCGAGGUGAGCCAGGGCCAGGGGGACCCCGGUAAAGUUUAGUUGAGGCUGGGGAAGGCCCUCGGAGCUCGUUUCCAGAUCGAGGUAAGAGGGACUUUCUUAAAGGCCUAGUCUAUGGGAUGGGGCGGCGGAGGGAAUUUUUUGAGAAAUAAAAUGAAGCUGCAGUGUACGUUA